UGAGCCACUGCGCCUGGCCAGAUCUAUUUAAUUAUGAAAUUAAAACAACUACUUCAUAACAAAACAAGAUAAAAUACAGCAGAAGUAUAUGAAGCCCCUCUUUGCCUGGCUCCAUACUAGGCAGCGGGGAUAGAGAGGAAUUAGACACUGUCCCUCCCCAAAUAACCAUUGCUAAUAAUUUGGCCAGCCUGGGCAACAUAGCAAGACUGUCUCUACAAAGAAUUUAAAAACUGGCCAAGCAUGGUGGUACACGCCUGUAGUGCCAGCUACUUGGGAGGCUGAGGCAAGAGGAUUGCUUGAACCCGGGAGGCGGAGGCUGCAGUGAGCCGAGAUUGUGCCACUGCACUCCAGCCUGGAUGACAGAGCGAGACCGUAGCUCAAAACAUAAUAAUAAUUUGAGAUGUGUCUUUUCAGGUUUUUUUUAACGUAUAUAUGAUAUAUAUGAUGACAUUUUGAAGUGUUCUGUGUUACACUGUCACCAGAGGUUUUGUCAUGCCUGGGAGAUUAUGAAUAAUGCCUCAUUUGCAGAUUUGGGUCAGAUGAGGGCUGAGUGAGAGUGGUUUUAGCCUGAUCGGUGAGUUUUCAUAGUCCCUGGUGGCUGUGUGUCACCCUUCUUCAUCUGAAGGUCCCCGGUGGUGCCAUUGUCUUUCCCUGCUCCCCGUCCCCAGCCAGCUCCACUUCCUGAAUUUUCCCCCUGUUUGAUGGUCCUACUGUUGUUAUGGUGACCUGACUUUGGUUAAUAAACAUGUAAUCAUAAGUAUAUGAGGCCCUCCUCUUCCUGGCUGCAUGCUAGGCAGUGGGGAUACAGAGGAAUUAAACACUGUCCCUUCCUUCAAGGAGGGCUGUGGUCUUUGCCCCCACCUUCUUCAGUCAUUUGGUAGGACUAGAACCAGUUCUGCCUCGAUGACUUCAUUCCCUCACUCUGUUACACACCUCACCUCCUCUUCCUUGCUCUCCCUGCUCUCCCUGUCUCUGUUGUAGGCCUUUCUCACCCUGCCCCGGGCUGUUCCAGCAGCCUCUUUCAGCCCUCUUGCUCUAGCCUCCAGUUUGUUCUUCACAUCACAGUCAGUUCCGUGGCCCCCAGGCACAGCUCCAGUCACACCCAGUCCCUCCCCAUCACCUAGGCCAGUGGUUCGCAGCAUACACUGCAGACCAUGGGGGUCCCCAAAACUCCUUUAGGAAUCUGCACAGUUAAAAUGAUUUUUGUAAUCGUACUAAGAUGCUGUCUGUUGCUGGAAAGCAACAAUGAGUAAGACUGUUGGUGCCUUGGUCAAGGUGGUGAUGCUGAACUGUGCCAGUAGCCACUAUAUUCUCCACUGCUAUGUACUCCCAGGUUUUUGUUUUUGUUUUUAUUUUGAGAUAGAGUCUCACUUUGUCACCCAGGCUGGACUACAACAGCAUGACCUCGGCUCACUGCAACCUCCGCCUCCCGGGUUCAAGUGAUUCUCCUGCUUCAGUCUCCUGAGUAACUGAGAUUAGAGACACCUGCCACCACAACCAGCUAAUUUUUGUAUUUUUAAUAGAGACAGAGUUUUGCCAUGUUGGCCAGGCUGGGCUCGAACUCCUGAACUCAGGUGGUCUGCCCACCUCAGCCUCGCAAAGUGCUGGGAUUACAGGCAUGAGCCAUCACACCCAGCUUUUUUUUAAUGCCAUUUUCACACAAGAAUGUCUUUGAUGAAGUAGCAAAAAUUGUCAGUUUUAUUGAAUUCCAACCCUGAGUACGGAUCUCUUUAAUAUUCUGUGUAACAAAAUAGAAAUGCUCAUAAAGUACUUCUGCGGCAAACCAAAGUAUAGCACCUGACUCAAGGAAAAGCAAGGAAAAGCACAUGUGGGAUCCCUUGAAUGGCAAGUGAAACUAGCCACUAGUUUCAUUUUUACAUGAAACAAUGGCUGUGUUGGGUGCUGAGGCUGGAAGGUAGACAGGGGCUUGGGGUUGGAGAGCCUCGUGGGCUGCGUUUGUGCUUGGGGGCCUUGAGCGCAGCCCACCUUUGUCAGCUUUCUACACGCUGCUCCCCACUCCCAUCCAGCCCUUUCCUCCUGCUUGCUCUUUCUUCAGCACACACUUCAUUCUCCCCUUCCAUGUCCUUCCUCUUGUUCCUUCCACCAGGAGAUGCAGUGACAGCUCUGAAGGCUGCCUGUGAUCCCAGAAUCAGAACAGAGGUAGAAGAUGGACUGGAGUUGUGACCUUUUGUCUCUAGGACUCUCAGGCCCCCAGUCCUGUCUGAGGCCUGUGGGGGAUCCUUUGCUGGCACCCUAGCAGGCCUCACCUGCCAGUUUCAUUGCAGCGGAGUGAAAUGCUGCCACCUGCAUGCUGCAGCCCAGCCUCCCCUCACACCAGACUCUUGGGGAAAGAAUACCUUAGCCCCUUGCAGUAUCGCUAUGGACAGACGGUCCUUUGAUUGAGCUGACUUUACAAGUGGCUCCUUUCAUCCAUCAUGUGUUAAAUCUGACUAGUGUCUGUUUGAGUGUACCCUUUCCUUGUCCCAGCAUAAUCAUGAUGCCACAAAACCAAAUCUUCCCACUAAUGGGUCAGACAGAAGAACGUAGCCUGUCCCUGACACCAGAACUGCCAUGAAAUAAUGUAGGUGGACUUUGGUUGGUAGCUCAUCUUUCAUAAGAUGACAAAACACAAAAUACAAGGCAAGCUCAGAGCAAGAAGAAGAAACUUCUGAUAAAUGAAGUUUUUGAUUAAUAGGACGAUGAUAAUGUGGUAAUAAUGCCUUCAUAUUUCCAGAAGCUAGGGCAGUGCUGCCCAACCUUUUCACAUCAUAGCACACGCUGAAAAUGAUACUGUUCUGCACACCUAAGUAACAGUGAGUGACUGGAGGCCUGAUGAGGGGAUCAAUACCUCAUUCACAGCACAUCAGCAGGGAAGCUCUGUGCUAAGGUUUAUAAACAAAAGCAUUCUCAUUGGUGCCUGGCUACUUUUACUAGCUACCCCUUCUGCCUUUCAGCAUUAAGGUUUAAAUACAGUGUAAUGGUUAAAAGCUUGAAUUCUGAGCCAGACCAUCUAGAUGUAGAUCUCAGCUCUGCCACUUACAAGCUAUGCGACCUUGAGCAAAUCAUUUAAUCUCUUUGUACUUCAGUUUCUUCAUCUGUAAAAUCUGGAUACUUAGCUCAUAAAGUAGUGAUGAUUAAAUAAGUUAGUAUAUGUAAAGUGUAGCGUUGGUAAAGUGCUUAGAAUGCUGCCUGGCCUACAGUAAGCAGCAUGUGUGUGUGUGAGUAAUGUCACUACUAGGAGUAGUCAUGUGGACUCUAAUACUGCUCCGGCUACUACUUCAAAGAUGUAAAUGUUCUGGGGUCAGUCUCCCCAGGUACCCCCUCAUUGCCUCCUCUGUCACAUUUCUUAGUCUUGGCCACUUCCUUAAGAGUGCCCAUGACACUUCCUUUCAGUCCCUCAGUUCCUGAUCAUUUUCUCCGUUCUCCAUUUGUUUUGGAAUGCUCAGCUAGCUGAUGCCCGAGAAGGCAGCUGGGUUGGUAAUUACACUUCUCUGCUUGCUCUCACCACUAUUUCUUCUCAAGAAAGCUCUUGUGGCUGAGGGAAAUCGCUCUUAAAGGUUGGGGAGACCUUGAAAAGAAUUCUGAAGUGGUUGGGAGAGGAGUGUGAGCUAAGUUUGCAGAGCUGAGCUAGCCAGCAAAGUCGGGUUCUCAGUGGGGAGAGGAUCAUCUCUGGUUUCAUGCACAGAUAUGAAAGCUGAUGAGUUCUCUGCAGGCUCUUCAAAAUUUGGAGUACAGAUCUGGUUCCUUUGGGGACAAUGUGGCUCAUAAGACUAUGGAGAAGUAACACAGUUCUUCCAGAGGGUGGGCCUCGAGGUCACUUUCUGGAGCAGAAUGGUGGAUGGAUGCUUGCAUGUCAGGAAUCUCUGUGCUGCAGUAGUCCUUCUAGGGAGCCUCCAUAACCCUUCCUCAUCUGCUCUAUGAGUUCUCUGUAAAUCUCCCCUGCAGGAACCAGGAUGAUUCCUGGAUCUGUAUCCUUCACACUUACUAUACCUUCAGUACCAUCAGUGCUCGUUCACUCACAGGUUUUACAAAGAGACGAAACAUGCAUUCCUAUUUUAAUGGAGAAAACAAGAUAAACGUAUGCCUAGGAAUGGAGACAUUUAUUAUCAUCGAUGACGAUGAGACUGCUUGUGAGCUAAUGUCAUCCCUCCUCCCAUGUGCUCUGUGCCCCUGCCAGCCUGAGUGAUCACCAGUGGCCCCCACCGGCCCUGUGUCCCUCCUCCAGGCCUCAGCCUGUGCCCUUCCUUGGUCUGGGACACUCUCUUCCAGGCCUCAGCCCUGUCCCACUCAUCCCUCAGGUAUUGAGGCUUAGCUGUGUCUUCCUCUAGUUACCCAACUGGGUUAGCUUCCUCUCUCCUGCUCCACAGCACCUGGUACCUCCCUGUCCCAGCACUUGUCCUACUAUGUUGAAAUUGUUUUAAGCGUCAGCAGCAGAUUUAAACGCCAUCAGGGAAGAGACUGUGUCUUCUCUUAUACUCUCACUGUCUAGCACCAGACGAUCAGUAGGUGCCCAAUAAAUAUAGCAUUAUUGAAGAGUAAGUCAGUGGUGCUUUCACUUCUAGUCUCUUAUUUGAUCCUCACAGCAGCCUUGUGGCAUGGGCAGCCCAGGCCUUCUGCUUACCUCAUUUCAUAUACAAGGAAACUGAUCCUCAGAGAAGCUAAGCAGCUUGCUGCAGUUCGUGCAGUGGAGGAGAGCCAUAGCUCUCAGGCUCCAAUGUUCAGCACAUUUUUUCAUUUGUUUUUAUAAAAUAUUUACUUUUAAGAAGUAGCAUUUUUUUUUUUUUUUUUGAGACGGAGUCUCGCUCUGUCGCCCAGGCUGGAGUGCAGUGGCGCGAUCUCGGCUCACUGCAGGCUCCGCCCCCCGGGGUUUACGCCAUUCUCCUGCCUCAGCCUCCCGAAUAGCUGGGACUACAGGCGCCCGCCACCUCGCCCGGCUAAUUUUUUGUAUUUUUAGUAGAGAUGGGGUUUCACCGUGUUAGCCAAGAUGGUCUCGAUCUCCUGACCUCGUGAUCCGCCCGCCUCGGCCUCCCAAAGUGCUGGGAUUACAGGCGUGAGCCACCACGCCCGGCCAAGAAGUAGCAUUUUUUAAAAAAUAAAAAUAACAUUGGUUGUUUUGAAUGAUUGCGAAAUUAGUAUCUUCAUGGCACCAAUAUUCCUAAAAUGUUUCUUUCAUCACUGAAUGUUGAAUUUUAAUACAGAGAAAUCUAGAAACAUUUUUAAAAACUAAAAUCAGAUACCAAAUUCCAAUGUGUAUUAGAGAAAGAUUAUGGUGUACUUUAUUUAAAAAUAAAACGUGAGUUAAACAAUAAUAGCAGGAAAAAUAAAUUUCAUUGUGUACAAUUUAGAGAAUACUGAAAAUAUAAAAAAGAAAAUAAAAAUCACCCCAUCACAUAGAGAAAACUCUUAUGGAUUAGAAAUGGUCUGGACUUGAAAGAGCAGCAUUGAGUUUGAAUCCCAGUUAAACCACUAACUAGAUGUUUGGCAUUGGGUAGGUUAUUUAAUCUACUGGCUGCCUGCUCUGAGCUUCUUUCCUUACCUGAAAUAUGGCAAAAAUAUUUACCUUUUGAGAUUAUGAUAAGAAUUAGAGAUAAUAUGUACAGAAUAUCCAUGUAGUUGGCACUUUUUAAAAUUGUAGCGUAUUAGCAGUUUUACGUAUUUCUGUCUAGUCUUUCUACUCUGUUGGGUUCAUAUAUGGGCAUACAUACCUGUGCAUAUGCAUAUGUUUUUGGAAACAUAUUUAUGUGAAGUAUAUCAUUGGGUAUUUUUUGUUUUUUUUUUGAGACGGAGUUUCACUCUUGUUGCGCAGGCUGGAGUGCAAUGGUGCGAUCUCAGUUCACCGCAACCUCCGCCUCCGGGGUUCAAGCAAUUCUCCUGCCUCAGCCUCCCGAGUAGCUGGGAUUACAGGCAUGCACCACCAUGCCUGGCUAAUUUUGUACUUUUAGUAGAGACGAGGUUUCUCCAUGUUGGUCAGGCUGGUCUCAAACUCCCAACCUCAGGUGAUCUGCCUGCCUCGGCCUCCCAAAGUGCUGGGAUUACAGGUGUGAGCCACCACACCUGGCCAUCAUUGGGUCUUUACAACAACCUGUGAGGUAGACAGGGCGGGUGUGUUUUUAAACCUAUUUGAUAGAUGAGGAAACUGAGACUCUAAGAGGCACAGUAACUUGGCCUUGGUUCUGUUAUAAUAUCUGAACCAGGGCUUCUGCCUUGCUCGCCUGAUGCCAAGCCUGUGUGCCUUCCCUGUCAGCAAGCAGCAUGCUGCUUCUUCAGUUCCACUUCCACCUCCACUAAUAGACACAUGUGGUGGACCGCCGAGCCGUUCCCAAGAGGAAGGCAAGGGCUGGAGGCAGCGGAAGUGCUGGGAGCCUCCAGACCAGCUGGGAUCUGCCUGAAACUGAAAAGAAGUGCUCACUUCUUCCUCUGUAAUAACAGACACAUUGCCCAAUCCUAUAGCAAGAACCAGGCUUCUGUUUAGAAAGUGAAGGACCUGGCUGGGCGCAGUGGUUCACGUCUGUAAUCCCAGCACUUUGGGAGGCCAAGGCAGGCGGAUCACCUGAGGUCAGGAGUUUGAGACCAGCCUGGCCAACAUGGCGAAACCCCGUCUCUACUAAAAAGUACAAAAAAUUAGCCGGACAUGGUGGCAUGUGCCUGUAGUCCCAGCUACUCUGGAGGCUGAGGCAGGAGAAUCGCUUGAACCCGGGAGGCAGAGGUUGUACUGAGCUGCACUCCACUGCAUUCCAGCUUGGGUGACAGAGCAAGACUCCAUCUCAAAAAGAAAAGAAAAGAUAAGAAAGUGAAGGACGUUUUGUGUCCUAGACCCUUUUUCGAAAGGGAGUUUAUCCAGGAAUUAGUAGAAUUCCUGAACUGGAUUCAUAAAACUAAGUAGCCUUACUCUGCAUUGUCUACAGGGCAAAGUUGUACCCAUGUUUCUUUCAGGAUGUGCACUGGGUACCUAAAAGGCCAGUGUGACAUACCCCACACCUAACAGUAUGCAUGUCAUUUCAUAUCAUUUCUAUUUCAGUGCAAUUUCUGAUGGCUGCUAUGUGUCUGACACUGUGCCAUGAUCUGUAGGAGAAACAAGUGAACAGGGGACAAUCUCAGCCUUUAGGAACACAGGGGAGCACUCAAGGCCAAAUAAAAUCAGUGCCCUCGUGGAGCUUCUCGCAGGGUGUUUGGGAGCAGAGGAUGGAGCACCAACUACUAGUUCUGCUCAGUAACACCCUCCAUUUGCAUAGCACCUAACUGACUUCCAGAGUCUCUGUAGAAACCUUAACUCAUCUGGAGUUAUCAGGGAGCUGCAAAAGGGUUGGGACUAUCGAGCCGGCUUUUGAUGACCAAGAAGAAUUCCUAGGCCAAGGGAAGCAGUUUCAGAAACAACUCUCCAAGUUCCAUUUCCAAGGAAAGUCUUAACCAUUUGUCCCUUCUGGCGUACCCUCUUUCAUUGAAAUCCAUGCAGAAUAUACCAGGUACUCUGUCUUUGUGUGUGUGUGAAGCCAUAAAAUCUAAUGUUACGUGUGCGGUGGUGCUGUGAGGUAUGCUUCUCGUGCAAGCGGCUCCCUCAGCCCUGCUGUGGUAAAGACCAAGUAUAAAUUGUCGCUAACAGGGUUUUCUCAUUAGAGUCGUGUGCCUGAGUGUCCCCUGUGAAUUAUAAUGCCUCCAGCCCUCUUGCUGCUCCUCUGCUCUGCCUGUCUUUUGGCUGUUUUGCUUGUCCUGGGGCCCUCCAUCAAAGUGUGGACAGGGGAAGGAGAAAGAGCUGAAACCCAAAUCUGUUUCCUCUGCACUGGGCCUGCGGUGCCGAUGAGAAAAUAGAUGCAGACACGGGUUGCCACUGGACUGCAUUCAAGAUCCCCAAAAUGGAUGGAAGAAUGCGCCUAAAUUGAGCUGUCAGGCACUUGGCUGCGUAACCAUGCUUUCUGGAUUGUGGUGUUGAAAGUGCCAUCCUGUGUGCUCUCUCCGGAUGGCUGUCACGUACUUGCGUCUGAGAACAGUAGAUGGGCAGUAGCGAACCCCUUCCCAUCGCAGAUGGUGACAGGAGGAGGAAGAAGAAGCGGAGGGGCCGGGCCACUGACUCCUUGCCAGGAAAGUUUGAAGAUAUGUACAAGCUGACCUCUGAAUUGCUUGGAGAGGGAGCCUAUGCCAAAGUUCAAGGUGCCGUGAGCCUACAGAAUGGCAAAGAGUAUGCCGUCAAAAUCAUCGAGAAACAAGCAGGGCACAGUCGGAGUAGGGUGUUUCGAGAGGUGGAGACGCUGUAUCAGUGUCAGGGAAACAAGAACAUUUUGGAGCUGAUUGAGUUCUUUGAAGAUGACACAAGGUUUUACUUGGUCUUUGAGAAAUUGCAAGGAGGUUCCAUCUUAGCCCACAUCCAGAAGCAAAAGCACUUCAAUGAGCGAGAAGCCAGCCGAGUGGUGCGGGACGUUGCUGCUGCCCUUGACUUCCUGCAUACCAAAGGCAUUGCUCAUCGUGAUCUGAAACCAGAAAAUAUAUUGUGUGAAUCUCCAGAAAAGGUGUCUCCAGUGAAAAUCUGUGACUUUGACUUGGGCAGUGGGAUGAAACUGAACAACUCCUGUACCCCCAUAACCACACCAGAGCUGACCACCCCAUGUGGCUCUGCAGAAUACAUGGCCCCUGAGGUAGUGGAGGUCUUCACGGACCAGGCCACAUUCUACGACAAGCGCUGUGACCUGUGGAGCCUGGGCGUGGUCCUCUACAUCAUGCUGAGUGGCUACCCACCCUUCGUGGGUCACUGCGGGGCCGACUGUGGCUGGGACCGGGGCGAGGUCUGCAGGGUGUGCCAGAACAAGCUGUUUGAAAGCAUCCAGGAAGGCAAGUAUGAGUUUCCUGACAAGGACUGGGCACACAUCUCCAGUGAAGCCAAAGACCUCAUCUCCAAGCUCCUGGUGCGAGAUGCAAAGCAGAGACUUAGCGCCGCCCAAGUUCUGCAGCACCCAUGGGUGCAGGGGCAAGCUCCAGAAAAGGGACUCCCCACGCCGCAAGUCCUCCAGAGGAACAGCAGCACAAUGGACCUGACGCUCUUCGCAGCUGAGGCCAUCGCCCUUAACCGCCAGCUAUCUCAGCACGAAGAGAACGAACUAGCAGAGGAGCCAGAGGCACUAGCUGAUGGCCUCUGCUCCAUGAAGCUUUCCCCUCCCUGCAAGUCACGCCUGGCCCGGAGACGGGCCCUGGCCCAGGCAGGCCGUGGUGAAGACAGGAGCCCGCCCACAGCACUCUGAAAUGCUCCAGUCACACCUUAUAGGCCCUAGGCCUGGCCAGGCAUUGUCCCCUGGAAACCUGUGUGGCUAAAGUCUGCUGAGCAGGCAGCAGCCUCUGCUCUGUGGCUCCAUUCAGGCUUUUUCAUCUACGAAGGCCCUGAGGUUCCCAUCAACCCCCAUUUCCCUAGGGUCCUGGAGGAAAAAGCUUUUUCCAAAGGGGUUGUCUUUGAAAAGGAAAGCAAUCACUUCUCACUUUGCAUAAUUGCCUGCAGCAGGAACAUCUCUUCACUGGGCUCCACCUGCUCACCCGCCUGCAGAUCUGGGAUCCAGCCUGCUCUCACCGCUGUAGCUGUGGCGGCUGGGGCUGCAGCCUGCAGGGAGAAGCAAGAAGCAUCAGUUGACAGAGGCUGCCGACACGUGCCUCUUCCCUCUCUUCUCUGUCACCCUCCUCUGGCGGUCCUUCCACCUUCCUCUGUCCUCCGGAUGUCCUCUUUGCCCGUCUUCUCCCUUGGCUGAGCAAAGCCAUCCCCUCAAUUCAGGGAAGGGCAAGGAGCCUUCCUCAUUCAGGAAAUCAAAUCAGUCUUCCGGUCUGCAGCACGGAAAAGCACAUAAUCUUUCUUUGCUGUGACUGAAAUGUAUCCCUCGUUUAUCAUCCCCUUUGUUUGUGAUUGCUGCUAAAGUCAGUAGUAUCGUUUUUUUAAAAAAAAAGUUUGGUGUUUUUAACCAUGCUGUUCCAGCAAAGAUGAUACCUUAAACUCCCACUGCAAGCCCAUGAACUUCCCAGAGAGUGGAACGGCUUGCUCUUCUUUCUAGAAUGUCCAUGCACUUGGGUUUUAAUCAGCAGUUCCCUAUUAUUCUGAUUUUAAGCUGUUCCUGUGAUGAACUUAGAGACAGCAUCGGUGUCUGCUGCUGUGUCCCCAGGUCUUGUGUGGGUGGCACAGAUCUGGGCAGUUAGAUAGUGCUCUGUGCCUAAGGUGAAGCCACACUAGGGUGAAGCCUCACUUCCCUGUUUGAGCAAUGCAGUGCCUGCUGCCCGUGUGCAUGAAGGUACAGCCAUUCAGAUAAGUGGAACUAUUGAGUUACAUAAAGAAAAUAGAUUUGCAUUUGUCAGGCAGACGUUUAUACAACACCACGGUGCUUUUAUACAUUGUGCUUAUUUUAAUAAAACUGAAAUUCUAUGUGUGGCCUA